UGACCUUAUCAUGGAGAAACACUGAAAAUACUAUCAAAUCUUUGUGGUCUGCAAACUCAGAGCUUCCAAAGCUUGAGAUAGGAAAUGACACUUCUGUUAAGCCUGAAUGUUGCAGGAUCUCGGGGAAAGGGAUAGUUGAGAUGGAAUAUACAUUUGUCGAUUCUGCAGACCAAGCUUUGCAGCGAGUGAUCGGGAGGAAUCGUAGACUUGCAUGUACUUACACCUCGCUCCCUGAGAUUCGGGAGGCACGGAAAAUUUUGGGAUGGCUGUUAAUUUAAAAUUUCAUCUGAAAGAGUCGAUUUGGAGUAACUUGUCACUACCAGUUGGUUUGCCAGUGACGUGUCUGCCAACUCAAAGAGUGCAAAGAUCAGAAGCUGAAAGAGGAAUUCUCAGAUCUUGUUUAAAAAUAUUUUGGCAGUUUUAAUAGAUAAUAUGAGAUUGCAUAGGAACAGAGGAGCCGAAUUUAAAAUAGAUUAGUCACGUAGGAAAUGCUUAGCUGUUGUAAAAGUGUUCACGCAAUGACUUACCUUCCUAGGUUUUCACUUUUUUGAAAAUUUUUCCCUGAACAACAUACUGAAUUAUGAUAUUUCAUAAUUUGUGUGUGGGUUAUAAGAAGUAUGAGGAGAGAGGAUGCAUAGGAUUUGCUUUUUCUGUUUUGGGUGGAGAUUGAGCUUUUCCUGAAGACCUGAAAGAGCUGCUUCUGAUCUAAUCUGAGUGCCAGUAAAAGUGGCUCUUAGAUGAAAGGCUUUUUCUUCUCCAUAUUGGUGUCAUUUAAGACAUACAAUAUUAUCUUUAAGUUUAAAAGAUUAUAUUUUUUCAUCGGUAUUAACAUACAAAUAAGGGUUUUCUUGAGUCUUUGUAGAUGACUGGCUAGGUCAGCCUUUUUUAUCCCUGAUUUGGGUAUUAGAUAUUGGAACAUUAGGUCUUGAAAGAAAAUUUCAAGGAACUUCUGGAAGAAGCUUUCUUGUUUCAAUUUUAUUAUUUUUACCAUUUUGCACUAAAGUUAAUAUGCCAUUUCGAGAUUAAAAAUGUUUUUUUCCCGACUCUGAUGGUCUCUUGUUACUUGUGAAGGUAUCAAUAAUAAUGUAAUAAUGACAACAUUGAGGAACUGUAGAUUUUUAUUUUAUUCUGCCUGCUAAUUAUGGAUGUAAUUCAAAUGACAGAAAUUCUUAGGAUUACUAUGGUUGUUACAAGGACAUUUAGUAAGCUUAUAUGUCUAGUAAAUAACUUGAUCUAUCUAAAAAAUACUUUAUCUCAUCUUAUUUCAAAAUUAUUCAGUUGAGUAAUCUCUUUUUUGUAAGUGGCAAAUAACAUCCACUGUCGUAUGAGAAAGUUAAUAGAUGUUUAUUCUCCUUGUUAGAGAAACACUGAAAGCAUUAGGUAUUUUCAUCACGGUAUAGCUAAGAACCUAUUGGUUUAUUAAAGAUUUUGGGGGUUUGCACUGUGGAUGCUUCUUUGAAAGAAGAAAUUAUAAACUGGGGGACAUCUUUGAUGAAUUUGUUAAUGAACUUUAAAUAUUUAAAGUUCAGGUUGGAUGAAAACAGAAGUAUGUCAGUUUCUAAAGAAAAUAUAGACAUGGGGUCUCGCUGUGUUGCCCAGGUUGGCCUCAAACUCCUGGGGCCAAGGGAUUAUCCCACCUUAGCCUCCGAAGUUAUGUCAGGUUUCAUUGGCCUAAGACUUAGGACUCAUUUAUUCCAUUAUAACAAGCCUGGAGCUGUUUUUUGUGAGUGCUAUUUAUGUACAUUUUUGGAAAUGAAAUCUUUGUAAAAUUUACCUUUAAAUGCAAAGCUGUGUUUUGGAUGGAAGUGACCAUUUUAUAAUAUGUUUUGAACAGUUUAAGAUCAUGCUAAUGUAUAAUCAACCCGUCUAUGCAUAUUUCAUUGUGGAAUUUGCUAAACAUAUUAUAGCAUAAAUAAUACCCACUUGAGCAUAAUAGAAGAUUGCUAGACCCUUUGCUUUGGAUUUAUUUUUAUCUUACCUGCUUCUUUUAUCCUUUUCAACAGUAGAAUGAAGAAUGGUACAAUUGUUAUAUUAAGUGCAAAUUCCCUUUCUGAUCUGACAUGUUCAAUAACUCAUACAACAGUAGAAUAUACUCCUUAAACUUAAUAAUGGAGCAAGUGGGAAAUUUGACAAGUUGAUGCUUGGAAAAAAUAGUAAUCCUCAUCUUGUGAGAAUUCACACAGCUAAAACAUGCCAUUAAGCUUUCAAAGAGUUUGUCAUUUCUCAAUACAUUGUAUUUAGGGGGUGACCCAUUAAUUUGCAUGGUAUAUUAAUUUAAUGAUUUUUACAGAGAAACUUCUGAAAAGGUGAAAAAAACUUAUAAAUAUUGCCUGCAUACUCUGUGCUCAGUGGGUACUUAAUGUUUGUUGAAUGACUUGAUGGUUGGUUGGUUAAGAAUUUCCAGCCAUUGUACGAAAUGCUAGUAUUUGCCUAUUGUUACUAUAGUUAAAUGAAUAAAUACAUAGUUAUCAUUUAGCAAAAUCUGGUUUAGUUUUUUCUAAUUUUGGCAAGUAAAUUUAACCUCACACUGAAUAUUUUUAUUAAAAUUUUAAGGUGUCUCUAAAAUUUUUUUCCAGCUUCAUUCAUUCCAUUCAGAAUUUAGAAACGAAUCAAUAAGAGACAACAUUUUAAGUUUCCCAAAUUACAGUCAAUUCAUUAGAAGGUAUAUAUUUAAUUCAUAGCUAAGAUCCAGAAGUAUCUUGACUUAUAUGGUACACCACUGAAUGCUUACUAAUAUGUGUGCCUAGGUAAAUCACUGGAAGCUUGAAACACAUACAUGGGAGUUAGUACCUAGGCCAACCCUACAAUCUUAAGUAACCCAUAAAGUGUAGCUGAACUAUAUUUAAUCAUUUUAGCUUGAGUUCUGGGUCUAGGAUGAGAAUAAAAGCGAAAAUAAUUAAUUGCAUAGAGCAAGCUUGUCCAACCCGAGGCCUGUGGUUGCAUGCAGCCCAGGAGGGCUUUGAAUACGGCCCAACACAAAUGCAUAAACUUUCUUAUCAGCUAUCGUUAGUGUAUUUUUUGUGUGGCCCAAGACAAUUCUUCUUCCAGUGUGGCUCAGGGAAGCCAAAAGAUUGGACACCCCUGACACAGAGGCUCAUCCUUCCCUAAAUCAAAUUCUUGUUUGUUAUAAACCUUUUCUGUUUCAGCCUCUCGUGUACCCAUUUCACCCUUCUCUCAGGCCCCUGUACCUUCAAGCUAUACUCUCCUGAACUUGGAAUACUUCAGAGGCUCUAAGUGUAGUCUUUCUGUCCUCAGAUUUCCUAUUUUCAUUGUCCCCAUUUCCCAUCUCAAUCUUUCAUUAAUGUGCAUCAGAUCUUGUCUAGAUGUUAAGAAGAAAACAAUCUGAUGGAACUAAUUUACCUUUAUCUGUAAAUGACUCAUGAGCUCUUAACUCUUCCCAAGGUUUUUCACAUUUUUUGUAAGUCUGUAAGAGGUUGCUAUUAACUCAGAUAAUUUUAAAGUAAAAAUUGCAGGCUGUGUUGGGGGAAGGAAUUUCUAGUCUUAUGCAUAAAUAAGUCAGGCCUUACUAGGAUUUUGCCCGUGGUUUCUUCCCACUCCUGGAAGUGUGUUCAUAUGUGUAUUGCUAUAUAUGUUUGUGUAUGUGUAUCUAAUAAUGAUUCCCAUAGCAUGGAGGGGAGAAGAUGCAAGAAUAGUGAUUAUAAAUCCCUUUGAGUGUAUGGAUCAUUAAUGAGAUAGAUAUUUGAUGAUAACUUACACCGUGUUUAAUUUAUAGGAACAGAGAAGAAAAAGACCUAGGAUCUCAUGACUGAACUUGAAUUCUUAAAAGGCAGGUGUUGGGGCCGGACUCGUUGCAUGAUGUAUAACACUAACCACUUGUAGUUCCUGUAUUGGCAGGAACUUUUGCUUUCUUGGGAGAAUAGCCAUGUUAUAGGAGUGCACCGUAUAGCUUUUUAAGAAAGAAGAAGUAUUAAGGAUGAGAGAAUGAAAAGGAUUGUAGGUAAAGUAACAGGAUGCCCUGUUAUUGGAUUGGCAAUUCAUUGAGAUACUGGUUUACACAGAAGGCCUCCCCUUUGGAAUAUGAAAGGUUGCUGAUCAGAUUCUGACUCAGACAUUGGGUUUCAUUGCACAGCAACCUUUCCAGAGAUGUUAUUCAUCAUUGAAACUUUGCUAGGAAUAAAUGGGGAUAAAAGAGUAAUGAAACCUAAUUCCUACCCUUGGGGUGCUUAUAACCUAACAGUGACUUGUUCUGCAGAGCCAGGCAGGUUGCCUUCCUUGUGCCAUGACUCCUUCACAGCUGCACAGCAUUUACCACAUUGUUUAAGUCUCUGCUUCUUGUCUCUCCUUGCUCUUAACUGACUCUCCAUGAAGGACUGUCUUUCCUCUGUUCCCCAGAACUGGCUUAGUUGUUGGUGUUAUUUGAAUAAGUUCAAAAUGUAAGAGAGACAAAGUGUUGCGGGGUUCAGAGAAGGGAGAUGACAGCUGCAGCCAGGGGUAGUGGGAAAGACAUUUUGGGAAAGGCUGUGAAGGUUGGAGGGAGAGAGGAUGCCUGGCACAGGGGCAGGGAAGUGGAAGGCAUAUUUGAGGAAUGCCUAGUGUAUCUGCUUGGCACAAGUAUAUGGGCAUGUUAAGGAACAGAGAGAAGGCUGGAAAGAUAGGCUUGGGUCUGGGAUGCCUAUAUGAGUAGUUUGGAUUUCUUUCUCUGCACUGGUGGAGAAGUUCGCAAAUCUGUAAACUUGGCAUUGCAGUGUGGGAUCUAUUGAAGGUGAAGGAGCUUUUUUCAAAAUUGGGGCAAGAAGCAAUGAACACUAGAAUUUGGUGCUUUUGAGGCAGAGAAAGAAGUGGUGGUGUAGCCUAAGGACAUGUAGAUUUGAGGAAGAAAGAAGAAAAAGCAAAAAUGGAAUCCAAACUUACUUAAAUCCGGGAAACUGAAAGACCAAUGGUGCAACUGAAAGAACUAAGAGAGUUGGAAAGAGUAGACUUGGGAAUCUGGAAGAAGGGCAGAAAAUGAGAGAAUGUACUUGAUUUUGGACACAUCAAAUUUGAGGUUUUGACAAUGCCCAGGUGGAAUGCCAAAUUACAGUUCAGAAGAACAGUUUGGGCUGAUGGUUCUGAACUUUUCAGGUGUGAGGAUAGCUUUUUAAAUAAAAACUUGCAAAUAUUUAUGACUACUUUUAGUAUUUGUUUUUUGAGAAUACAUGUAAAGACAAAACAAAAAUUCAGCUAUACUGUUAAGUGAGUUUUACUGAAUAACAGAAGUGUCUAUUUACCUUCAUUUGCAAAGUAGACGUGUGUGAGAGGCAUCUUUUUCACUCAGCAGUUGGUGCUUUGUGUGUAUUUGGAUUUGAGAACACUUGGAGUGACUCCAUGGCUCUUGUCCAAGCUACAAAUACAGAUUUGGAGGUCAUCUGCCUAUAGUGAUAAUUAAAGCCUGGGAAUGGGUGAGAUCAUCAAAAGAAAAUUAUGGACACACAAUAGAAAAGAGAUGUAAUAUAAAAAUUUGGAGAAUUCUUAGAAUAUAAUAGGUGAAAGAAGGAAAAACAAAUAAUAUAGCAUUACCAAAGUAAGGUGAAGAGCAUCUCAAGGAGUGAUACCAUGCAGCAGACAGAUUAAUGAGAGAGAGGCCCAGAGUUUUGAUAGAAUGGUGAGCCCAGAAAACAAGCUGGCCUGAGUCAGGUUUGAAGGAAUGGUUCUUCUUUUCUCUAGUGACAAUUAAAGCCCUCUGUCCUAUCAAAAAAUCCUCACAUCCCAGCUUGGAGACUGUCAGGGAAAUUUUGUUUUCCAUAGCGAAACAGGAGUUGACCGGUAGUUUUGUGGGCCAGACUAGCUCCCUGCUUCACUUAGCACAGUUGGAAUCUGGCAGGUGACUGAUGCUACCCUGUAAGGAGCCAAAGUGAAUUUUAAAAAAAGUUUUGGAACAAAUGAUUACCGUUUAAAAGAUCAGUGAAUAACAACAACAAAUGGUCUUAAAUUAAUGCAUUGUUUAAUUCCUCUUCCCCUAACAUCAUUGGGAUUCUUUUUAUAGGACUGAGCAGGGGGAGGAACAUUUAAGCUGAUGGAAGUGGAAGUGGAAGUUGCUGUACAUUGGCAGCAAGGCCUCCGAGUUAGCUUUUGAAUGCAGUUAACUGGUUUCUCUUAACUGUGGAAUUCAUUGAAAAGUCAGACUCCGAGUGGUCGUUCCAGGAUAUCUUGAAAAGCCCAGGUUAAACCCAUCCAGAGUAAUGGCUGCGGCCUUACCCAGGACCCUGGGGGAGUUGCAGCUGUAUAGAAUAUUACAAAAAGCCAAUCUACUUUCUUAUUUUGAUGCCUUUAUCCAACAAGGUGGUGAUGAUGUCCAGCAACUCUGUGAAGCAGGAGAAGAGGAGUUUUUGGAAAUCAUGGCACUCGUGGGCAUGGCUAGCAAGCCCCUUCAUGUUAGAAGGCUGCAGAAGGCUUUGAGAGACUGGGUCACAAACCCUGGGCUUUUCAAUCAGCCACUGACUUCCCUUCCUGUCAGUAGCAUACCCAUCUAUAAAUUACCAGAGGGAUCACCAACAUGGCUGGGAAUAUCCUGCAGUAGUUAUGAAAGGAGUAGCAAUGCCCGGGAACCUCAUUUAAAAAUCCCCAAAUGUGCUGCCACCACCUGUGUGCAGAGCUUGGGACAGGGGAAGUCAGAUGUGGUUGGGAGCCUAGCACUGCAGAGUGUUGGUGAGUCCAGACUCUGGCAAGGCCACCAUGCCACUGAGAGCGAGCACAGCCUCUCCCCAGCAGACCUGGGCUCCCCCGCGUCCCCAAAGGAGAGCAGUGAGGCGCUGGAUGCUGCUGCUGCGCUCUCUGUGGCUGAGUGUGUGGAGCGGAUGGCCCCCACACUGCCAAAAAGUGACUUGAAUGAAGUGAAAGAGCUGCUAAAAACCAACAAGAAGUUGGCCAAAAUGAUUGGUCACAUCUUUGAGAUGAACGAUGAUGAUCCACACAAAGAGGAGGAAAUUCGGAAAUACAGUGCAAUAUAUGGCAGAUUUGACUCAAAGAGGAAGGAUGGGAAACAUCUCACACUUCAUGAGCUCACUGUUAAUGAAGCGGCUGCUCAACUCUGUGUGAAGGAUAAUGCCCUGCUGACAAGAAGAGAUGAGCUUUUUGCCUUGGCUCGACAGAUUUCUCGAGAAGUCACCUAUAAAUAUACUUACAGAACCACCAAGUCAAAAUGUGGAGAAAGAGAUGAAUUAUCCCCAAAGAGAAUUAAAGUGGAGGAUGGGUUUCCAGAUUUCCAGGAUUCUGUGCAAACACUCUUCCAGCAGGCUAGAGCUAAGAGUGAAGAACUUGCAGCUCUUAGUUCACAGCAGCCUGAAAAGGUGAUGGCAAAGCAGAUGGAGUUCCUUUGCAACCAAGCUGGCUAUGAGAGACUGCAGCAUGCCGAGAGGAGGUUGUCUGCAGGGCUUUACAGGCAGAGCUCAGAAGAGCACAGUCCUAACGGCUUGACUUCCGAUAACUCAGAUGGACAAGGAGAAAGACCUUUGAAUCUCCGAAUGCCUAAUUUACAGAACAGACAACCCCAUCAUUUUGUGGUGGAUGGGGAGCUGAGCAGACUUUACCCCAGUGAGGCAAAGUCCCACUCAUCAGAGAGCCUUGGGAUUUUAAAAGACUACCCUCAUUCAGCUUUUACCUUAGAAAAGAAAGUCAUCAAAACAGAGCCUGAAGAUUCAAGAUAGCUGUGAUUUCUCUCACCGUUCUCUGGAAAUGGCAUCAGAUUUAAGGAUAAUACUCCAUCAUAGAAAUAAGCCUUAAUAACCAGUGUUGCCUCAUUCAGCUCAAACAGAUUUCAUAGCCAAAGCAAAAGGACUGGUACGGUAGUCUGUGGAAACCAGGAAGAUAAAACAACAGCCACAAAAGAGAAAAUCAAGAGUGUUGCAAUCUAUAACAGUAAUAUUGAUUCAUUCACAUUCCUGUGUUAAGUCAUUUUAUAUGGAAAGGCUUACAAAUCAAUAUUGUAAGCAUUCAUUAUUUAAGAAUGUACAAUGUAUUUGUGUAAUUUAUAGAAGUAAAAUCUAGAUGUUGAGACCUGUUUGGUCUAAUAGAUGUGGAUACAGUUUAUUUUACUUGAAAUUUUGUUGUCUACUUUGUGUGUUUAACGUAAAUAUAUGUCAGAGUUUAGAAUCUGCCUGCAGUUGUGAAAAAGAAAGCUUAAGUGAUGCAGUUAUUGGCAAGAUUGCAAUGAUUAUGGAAAAAUAGAAAGCGAAUACUCAGUUUAAGCCAAGGAAAAUAUUGUGGAUUUAAUAUUUGAUAAAACUGAUUUUGUUUAACAGGAAAUUUUUAGCAUUCAGUCAUAUAACAUCUGGUUAUCAAUGCACGUUUACACAAUAAAUACUUGAGUGGAGGAAAGUUAAAAAGAUGAGCAAUAGAGUAGAAAAUAUAUCUUAAACUAGUUGACCUAGAUUGUAUUAAUAGCUACUUAAGAUGUUUCAAAGAUAGGAAGCUAUUGCUUGGACAGAGAACUUGAAAUAAGUGGACCCAUGUAUAAAAGCUUUGACUUAAACAUUGAUAUUUCAGAAUGUGUUAAAUAGAUUAAGACACAGUAAGUUAACCCUACAUGUUAUAAAGAUGGCGACUGUUAACAAAGGCUGUAACAGAUUAAGUACUAUUUUAUAUCCAGAAAGUCUUCUCUAUGUAGAGAAGUCAGAGAGACUAGAUGCUUUCACUAGGGAAUGUCUUCCCACCCAGCCAUCACAAAUGUGGACAAUCACUGCAUCCACAUCUGUAGGCAUAUUUCUAUGGAAGUUUAAUUGACAGCUAUAUUCAUUAUUUAUUUUACAAUUUCAUUUUUCUACACCUUUGAGAUUUAUGAAUGCAGUUUUUUCUUAAAAUUUAUUUUAACUUGACAGUAUGUUUUUAGUUCCCCCAAUUUAAUUAAUGGACCAUGUGCAUAUAUAUGGGAGUGUGCUUACAUGUUAAUAAUUUACUUGCAUACUUAUGAGAAUUUCACAUUGGAAUUCAUAAUGGUAAAACAACAUACAUCUGCCAAUAUACGUUUUUUCUGUUGGUUUAAGAGAAGAUAACUGACAGCUUUACCUACUUCCUACAGAUGCAUCUAAACCCAGAUAUUACUGAGAAGAGUGUAUUGACUCUGAGUGUAAGAGAGUAUGUGUUUUUUUGUUUUUAGUUCUGCUCUAGAUCAUAAUUGUAAAAAAUAUUAAGUCAUAAUCUGUUACACUAAAAUUUGUCAGCCAAAUGUUAGAUGAAAUGUCUGCACUGUAGUCUCAGAUCACUGUCACGUAUAUAAAUUGCUUCUUCAUUUUAAUUUGUAGAAGUACUUUACAGUAGGAAACGCCAGUAAACAACUUUUAUACUGUUAAAAGGCUUUUUUCCCCUUCCUAAAUGUUUUAAUUGUACCAUAGUGUUUUGCUCACUGAAGAAGCUUCUUAUGGACCUUGCAACUUUGUUGCUAGCUUGAGGUUGAUUAUUGUGGUUGUAUUGUUCACUGUGUGUAGAAAUAGUAUGAGUACGAUUUCAAUAGACUGUUCAGUUUUUAAUAUUAGCCAUAGCACUGGUUAGUAUAUCUCAGUAGUUUCAUGAAACGUUUCCUGUAUUCUAAUCUAUUUUGAAACAUUUUGUUUUUUUUUAAUUGUGUCUUACAGUCAAGUUUGUAGAUUUUCAUAAGCCACAAUUUUAAAAGAUGCAGUAAUCUUCCAACUUCCAAUAUUUAUCCAUUCGUUGUGGACCCACAGAUUGCAUCUUUAAAUUCAUAAUAAGUUUCCUUAACUAUCUUAUGUUUCUAGUCUUUCAAGCUUAGUGAUAAGGUGGAAGCACAAGAAAAAUUUCAGUAGAAUACAGUUUUUAUUUUGUAAACACUAAUGUAUUAAACUUGCUAUACAUUAAAGCAAAUAAUAUAUAUUUUUAUUUGAAUUGUAUAUGUGAAUUGGAAGUUAUAAUUAGUUGAUUUUUUCAUUUUGUUAGAGGUAUUUUCACUGAACAAGGUCAAUUGGUUACCUCAGUAUUACAGCCAAUAUAGUCCAAGGGACCAUUUCUCCCCGAGUCUCUUACACUUUAUUGUGCGAUGUCCACGUUUUUGUGACUCUUCAAGCUGUUGGUGAGGUGGGACGAAUGCACUUGCUUCCUGUGGCAAUAAAGAUUUUCUGUGCCUCACA